GCAUUUCUUCUCUGUGCCCACCACCACACCCAGCUAAACCUGUCACGGGCUGGGUCUGGAAUUCCCCAUGAGUCCUGUGACCUCAGCCCACGCGGGGACCUACAGGUGCUACGGCUCACUCAACUCCGACCCCUACCUGCUGUCUCACCCCAGUGAGCCCCUGGAGCUCGUGGUCUCAGGACCCUCCAUGGGUUCCAGCCCCCCACCCACCGGUCCCAUCUCCACACCUGCAGGCCCUGAGGACCAGCCCCUCACCCCCACUGGGUCGGAUCCCCAAAGUGGUCUGGGAAGGCACCUGGGGGUUGUGAUCGGCAUCUUGGUGGCCGUCGUCCUACUGCUCCUCCUCCUCCUCCUCCUCUUCCUCAUCCUCCGACAUCGACGUCAGGGCAAACACUGGACAUCGACCCAGAGAAAGGCUGAUUUCCAACAUCCUGCAGGGGCUGUGGGGCCAGAGCCCACAGACAGAGGCCUGCAGUGGAGGUCCAGCCCAGCUGCCGACGCCCAGGAAGAAAACCUCUAUGCUGCCGUGAAGGACACACAGCCUGAAGAUGGGGUGGAGAUGGACACUCGGGCUGCUGCAUCUGAAGCCCCCCAGGAUGUGACCUACGCCCAGCUGCACAGCUUGACCCUCAGACGGAAGGCAACUGAGCCUCCUCCAUCCCAGGAAAGGGAACCUCCAGCUGAGCCCAGCAUCUACGCCACCCUGGCCAUCCACUAGCCCGGAGGGUACGCAGACUCCACACUCAGUAGAAGGAGACUCAGGACUGCUGAAGGCACGGGAGCUGCCCCCAGUGGACACCAAUGAACCCCAGUCAGCCUGGACCCCUAACAAAGACCAUGAGGAGAUGCUGGGAACUUUGGGACUCACUUGAUUCUGCAGUCGAAAUAACUAAUAUCCCUACAUUUUUUAAUUAAAGCAACAGACUUCUCAAUAAUCAAUGAGUUAACCGAGAAAACUAAAAUCAGAAGUAAGAAUGUGCUUUAAACUGAAUCACAAUAUAAAUAUUACACAUCACACAAUGAAAUUGAAAAAGUACAAACCACAAAUGAAAAAAGUAGAAACGAAAAAAAAAAACUAGGAAAUGAAUGACGUUGGCUUUCGUAUAAGGAAUUUAGAAAAAGAAUAACCAAUUAUUCCAAAUGAAGGUGUAAGAAAGGGAAUAAGAAGAAGAAGAGUUGCUCAUGAGGAAAAACCAAAACUUGAAAAUUCAACAAAGCCAAUGAAGCUCAUUCUUGAAAAUAUUAAUUACAGUCAUAAAUCCUAACUACAUUGAGCAAGAGAAAGAAAGAGCAGGCACGCAUUUCCAUAUGGGAGUGAGCCAGCAGACAGCCCAGCAGAUCCUACACACAUUUUCACAAACUAACCCCAGAACAGGCUGCAAACCUAUACCAAUAUACUAGAAAAUGCAGAUUAAAUGGAUGAAAUAUUCAAAACUGGAGUUUACAUAAUGAACGUAAGAGUAAUCAGAGAAUCUGACUCAUUUUAAAUGUGUGUGUAUGUGUGUGUAUAUAUAUGUGUGUGUGUGUGUGUGUGUGUGUGUGAAAAACAUUGACUGUAAUAAAAAUGUUCCCAUCGUAUCAACUCCA